GCUGGCGAGCGCCGCCGCCGGUGGAGACCGACGCUUGGCCAGAGCCAGCCCGCGGCGCCCGGGCCUGGCCGGCUGCUUCCCGCCUCAGCCGCCGCCCCCGCCUCCGCCGCCGCAGACUUUGCCUAGGCGGGCGAAGCUGAACGUGAGGUCCCUCGGCCCUGCGCGGUCCGGCGCGGCCCGGAGCCGCGGCGCAGGAGCACUGUGGCUAUUUGAAAUGAUAGACAAACUUAGACUUCAUCAUACAUGCUGGGAGUGUCUGCUGAUCACUUGGAGUGCUGUCCCUUGGAACAGGAGGAGUAAGAUUGAGCACCCCUGCAGUGGACCAUGAGUCGGUAAUGCCCACUGAGGACCUCUGGGAGCCAUGUCAGACGAAUCUGCCUCAGGGAGCGAUCCAGACCUGGACCCGGACGUGGAGCUGGAGGAUGCGGAAGAGGAGGAGGAGGAGGAGGAGGUGGCAGUGGAGGAGUGUGACAGGGAUGAUGAAGAAGACCUGCUGGAUGACCCAUCCCUGGAAGGCAUGUGUGGCACUGAGCAUGCCCAGUUGGGAGAAGAUGGGCAGCAGCCGCCGCGGUGCACUUCAACUACCUCAUCUCAGUCUGAGCCUUCAGAGCAGCUUAGGCGCCACCAAGGCAAGAACCUAGCCUCCGAGGACCCCAAAAAGAAGAGAGCUCAGAAGCCCUCCCACAUGAGAAGAAACAUACGAAAGCUACUCCGGGAGGAUCAAUUGGAGCCUGUUACCAAAGCAGCACAGCAAGAAGAGUUGGAAAGAAGGAAGCGCCUGGAGCAGCAGAGGAAAGAUUAUGCAGCCCCUAUUCCUACUGUUCCGCUGGAGUUCCUCCCUGAGGAAAUUGCUUUAAGGGCAAGUGACGGUCCCCAACUGCCUCCUCGGGUCUUGGCCCAGGAAGUCAUUUGUUUGGACAGUAGCAGUGGCAGUGAGGAUGAAAAAAGCAGUCGAGAUGAGGUGAUUGAACUGAGCUCUGGAGAGGAGGACACUCUGCACAUUGUGGACAGCAGUGAAUCUGUCAGUGAAGAUGAUGAGGAAGAAGAGAAGGGUGGCACCCAUGUCAAUGAUGUCUUAAACCAGCGUGACGCCCUUGGGCGGGUCCUUGUCAACCUAAACCACCCUCCAGAGGAGGAAAAUGUCUUCCUUGCCCCACAGUUGGCACGGGCUGUGAAACCUCAUCAGAUUGGCGGGAUCCGGUUCCUUUACGAUAACCUAGUGGAGUCUCUGGAGAGGUUUAAGACCAGCAGUGGCUUUGGCUGUAUUCUGGCCCACAGCAUGGGUCUGGGGAAAACUUUGCAAGUGAUCUCUUUCAUCGACGUCCUCUUCCGCCACACGCCAGCCAAAACAGUCCUUGCCAUUGUGCCGGUUAAUACUCUUCAGAAUUGGCUGGCAGAGUUCAACAUGUGGCUUCCACCUCCUGAAGCCCUCCCGGCUGACAACAAGCCUGAAGAAGUCCAGCCUCGGUUCUUUAAAGUUCACAUCUUGAAUGAUGAGCACAAGACGAUGGCAUCUCGUGCUAAAGUGAUGGCUGAUUGGGUGUCAGAGGGUGGCGUGCUGCUGAUGGGGUACGAGAUGUACAGACUCCUCACUCUGAAGAAAUCAUUUGCCACAGGUAGACCGAAGAAAACCAAGAAGCGUUCUCACCCAGUCAUCAUUGAUCUAGAUGAGGAAGAUCGGCAGCAGGAGUUUCGGAGAGAGUUUGAGAAGGCUUUAUGCCGCCCUGGCCCUGAUGUAGUAAUCUGUGAUGAGGGACACCGCAUCAAAAACUGCCAGGCCAGCACCUCACAGGCUCUGAAGAAUAUCCGCUCUCGCCGCCGGGUGGUGCUGACUGGGUACCCUCUGCAAAACAACCUCAUUGAGUACUGGUGCAUGGUGGACUUUGUGCGCCCAGACUUCCUUGGCACCCGGCAGGAGUUCAGCAACAUGUUUGAACGCCCUAUCCUGAAUGGGCAAUGUAUUGACAGCACACCUCAGGACGUCCGCCUCAUGCGGUACCGGAGCCAUGUCCUGCACAGUCUUCUGGAGGGCUUUGUGCAGAGGAGAGGCCACACUGUGCUGAAGAUUCAUCUCCCUGCCAAGGAAGAAAAUGUGAUCCUUGUGCGGCUCUCCAAGAUCCAGCGAGAUUUGUAUACACAGUUCAUGGAUCGCUUCCGGGACUGUGGUAGCAGCGGUUGGCUGGGGCUGAACCCCCUUAAGGCAUUCUGUGUGUGUUGCAAGAUCUGGAAUCACCCUGAUGUGCUGUAUGAAGCCCUUCAGAAGGAGAGCUUGGCCAAUGAGCAGGACCUAGACGUGGAAGAACUUGGCUCUGCAGGGACCAGUGCCCGCUGUCCACCACAGGGAACAAAAGGCAAGGGAGAGGAUAGCACCUUGGCUUCCUCGAUGGGAGAGGCAACCAAUAGCAAGUUCCUACAGGGCGUUGGCUUCAACCCUUUCCAGGAGCGAGGCAACAACAUUGUCACAUAUGAAUGGGCCAAGGACCUUCUGACUAAUUACCAGACUGGAGUCCUAGAAAACUCUCCCAAGAUGGUACUGCUUUUCCACCUGAUUGAGGAAAGUGUGAAGCUUGGGGACAAGAUCCUUGUGUUUAGCCAGAGUCUUUCCACCUUGGCUCUCAUCGAGGAAUUCCUUGGAAAACGAGAAGUACCCUGUCCACCUGGUACCGAGGGGCAAGGAGCACAGAAGUGGGUUCGAAACAUCAGCUACUUCCGGCUAGAUGGUAGCACCCCUGCCUUUGAGAGGGAGCGGCUUAUUAAUCAGUUCAAUGAUCCCAGCAACCUCACCACCUGGCUGUUCCUUCUCUCUACAAGGGCCGGAUGCUUGGGUGUGAAUCUGAUUGGUGCCAACCGAGUGGUGGUGUUUGAUGCUUCCUGGAACCCUUGCCAUGAUGCCCAGGCAGUAUGUCGGGUAUACCGUUAUGGCCAGAAAAAGCCCUGUUACAUCUAUCGCCUUGUGGCUGAUUACACUCUAGAAAAGAAGAUCUAUGACCGUCAGAUUUCCAAGCAGGGCAUGUCAGAUCGGGUGGUGGAUGAUCUAAAUCCAAUGCUGAACUUCACACGGAAAGAGGUGGAAAACCUACUGCACUUUGUUGAGAAGGAGCCAGCUCCCCAAGUUUCCUUGAACGUAAAGGGGAUCAAGGAGUCAGUCCUGCAACUGGCCUGUCUGAAGUACCCUCACCUCAUCACCAAGGAGCCUUUCGAGCAUGAGUCAUUGCUCUUGAACCGAAAGGAUCACAAGCUAACCAAGGCUGAGAAAAAAGCAGCAAAGAAAAGCUAUGAGGAAGACAAACGCACAUCAGUCCCCUAUACCCGCCCAUCGUAUGCGCAGUAUUACCCUGCCAGCGAUCAGAGCCUGACCAGCAUCCCCGCCUUCAGCCAGAGAAACUGGCAGCCAACUUUGAAGGGUGAUGAAAAGCCUGUGGCCAGUGUUCGUCCUGUGCAGUCCACCCCCAUCCCCAUGAUGCCCCGGCAUGUCCCAUUGGGAGGAAGUGUAAGCUCUGCCUCCAGCACAAAUCCAUCCAUGAACUUUCCCAUCAACUACUUGCAGCGUGCAGGAGUCCUUGUGCAGAAGGUGGUCACCACGACAGAUAUUGUUAUUCCUGGACUCAACAGCUCCACAGAUGUACAGGCAAGAAUUAAUGCUGGUGAGAGCAUCCACAUCAUCCGUGGGACAAAAGGGACGUACAUCCGUACCAGUGAUGGACGGAUCUUUGCUGUCCGGGCAACUGGCAAACCAAAGGUUCCUGAAGAUGGUCGGAUGGCUGCCUCAGGUUCCCAGGGACCUUCUUGCGAGUCCACAAGCAACGGCAGACACAGUGCCUCAUCACCCAAAGCCCCCGACCCUGAGGGGCUGGCCAGGCCCGUCUCUCCUGACAGCCCAGAGAUCAUCAGUGAGCUUCAGCAGUAUGCAGAUGUGGCUGCUGCCCGGGAAUCCCGUCAGAGCUCCCCAAGCACCAAUGCCGCCCUGCCUGGCCCCCCGGCCCAACUUAUGGACAGCAGUGCUGUUCCCGGGACAGCUCUCGGAACUGAGCCUCGACUAGGGGGUCAUUGCCUCAAUAGUUCCCUCUUGGUGACUGGCCAGCCCUGUGGUGACAGGCACCCAGUGCUGGACUUAAGGGGCCACAAGCGAAAGUUGGCCACACCACCUGCUGCCCAGGAGUCAUCCCGCCGGCGGUCCAGGAAGGGUCAUCUGCCAGCCCCCGUGCAGCCGUAUGAACACGGGUAUCCAGUCUCUGGCGGGUUUGCCAUGCCACCCGUCUCCUUAAACCAUAACCUCACCACCCCCUUCACCUCCCAGGCUGGGGAGAACUCCCUGUUUAUGGGCAGUACCCCCUCCUACUACCAGCUGUCCAAUUUGCUGGCAGAUGCCCGCCUGGUGUUUCCAGUGACUACUGACCCUCUGGUGCCAGCAGGCCCCGUCAGUUCCUCUUCCACGGCUACCUCAGUCACUGCCAGCAACCCCUCCUUCAUGCUCAACCCUUCUGUGCCAGGGAUACUACCCAGCUAUUCACUCCCAUUCUCACAGCCACUCCUGUCCGAGCCGAGGAUGUUUGCGCCUUUUCCUUCCCCUGUCUUGCCCAGCAACCUUUCGCGGGGCAUGUCUAUCUAUCCAGGCUACAUGUCCCCACAUGCAGGCUACCCAGCUGGUGGCCUCCUACGGUCCCAGGUGCCUCCAUUUGACUCUCAUGAGGUUGCCGAGGUUGGGUUCAGCUCCAAUGAUGAUGAGGAUAAAGACGAUGAUGUGAUAGAGGUCACUGGGAAAUAGCUAGGGAGCCCCUCCCCACCUCACUUGGGGCCCCCAGCAGGUUGCCCACCAAGCUGAAAGGCAGUGAUUUAGACCUUUUGAGAAUAGGACACUUGGCAGGAGGGAAAAGGAAGAGGACAAAGGAGGGUGGUUGGCCAAAGUGGCAGAGCUCUGUUGCUGUUUAACAAAAGAGGCAAAAAAAAAAAAAAAAAAAAAAAAGUCCAACACAGCAGCAAUAGCGGGAAAUCAGGGACCCAAAACAGGGAUGGAGGGGCAGUGCAGCCUCUUUUCCUUCCUGCCUUGCUUAUGCUGUCUGCUUGCUUGCUCGCCCAUCUGAGUGUAGAAGCGCACAUCCCAUUUCUGUCUUUGGGAACAUUCUUUCCCAAGAGAGCUGCCUUACUAGGUGACUUAGCUUGGCCUGGGGAGGGGAGUGAAGGAAGGGAGAAUGAGUGAGAGAAGGAGGGUGGGUAGGGGGAGCAGACUGUGAUCCCAUGUGAAGUGGGGUCUUUUUAGGGGGUGGGAAGGAAGCUGACCAGGUAUGUGUGUUUGUGAGUGUGUGUGUGUAUGUUUAUUUUGUAUGUGUAUGUAUGGAACAGAGCAGGGGUGAAGGUGGGAGGGGAGGGAGGGAAGAACUAAGAGGGAAACUGAAAAAUGAAUUUAUCUUUCUUUAAAUGGAAGUCAGUUUGGUGGUUCAUGGCACCUAGUGUGAACAUCAGGGUGAGCCCAGAAGAGCCAUGGAAAUAACAAGUUUCCUUCGGGAUGGGUGAAGAGAAGGCCCAGCUAACUCAAGUCCCUGGUAUUCAGAGCCACAUUUGUGUGAGAAUUUGGGGAAAUUCAUGAGAGAAAAUGGGCAUUACCAAUCUAUGUCUCUUAACCCCGGUGGCUAUCUCUGAGCAGCUCUCCCUUUCCAGCUUGGAAGGUUGUCUGUGUGCAGAGGCUGGGAGGGAGAAGCACUGCAGUACGUGAAUGAAAGGUCGCAGAGUUGUGGCUGGAAAAUACAUUUUUCACCAGGGUAGAACUGAGCCCCCAGCUGCCUAUCCUGGUAGUCUUUUCUGUUCCUUUCCUUCCCCUUUAGAGAGCUCCAUGUUAAUUUAUUUCUUAUGGGCAAUUAUUUAUUACUUGGACUUUUCAUGUGUCUUGUUUAUUUGGGGGUGGGGGGAGGUUAGGGGUAAGGAGGGUAGGUGAUAGAAAGGGAAGUUUUAAGAUAUCCCAGACCCUAUAGCCACUGGUGAAAAACAAUCCUGGAUGGAUGGUAAAUUGACCAGGGGAAGAGUUAGGUUUGACCAAGGUUUGGAUUAAACAACUAUAUUUUUGAGAGAUGGCUUUUCAGGAAGAUCAGGGAAUCCUGAGACUGGAUAGUUAGUGGAGGGUGGGACUCAUUCCACAGAAAUCGAAAGUUGUGAUCAUGGAGUUUGCAAUUGGGAAGUAAGAGACCCCAGAUUUGGAGCUGUGUCCUCCUGGGAUGAUGUUAGAUGUUGGCUCUCUAUGCUGAAUAGUGAAGCUGUGGAUAGGCGGUUGCUGGGUUGAGGGACUGUUGAUUUCAUGUUCGAAAAUAUCUUCAGGUGGUCCAUGUAGGCCUGGUGUCUGCUGCCUCCAUCUUUGAAGGAACAUGGAGGAGCCCUUUCUCUGUAGGAGCCCUAAGUCUGGGUUUUAUCUUAAAAGAACACACCAGUCAUUCUGGGUCUCCCCUUAUUGCCAUUGCCAGGGGAGGGUCGUCUAGUCCUUAAGCAUAAACACUGGCUGUCUUCCUACUGGUGUCCCCGCCCCCUCUGUAUCCCCCACCCCAACACUUUGCCAGACAGUUCUUUAUGAUGAACAAACUUUGGCUUUAGAGCUUUACCACUUACCCAUGGCUCCCUCCUUACUGGGCAGGUGGUGUACCUGCCUCUUCCCAGCCCAGAAGGCAGCUUAGUCAGGUCAUCCCAGUAGUAGCUCCUACAGCUCUUCUGACCAGCCCAUUUCCAUCUUUGGAGGGCCUUAGCAGACUCUGGGGUAUUGUCCUCAGAGAAGAGACAAGGAGAUGAUGGAUGGGGUGCAUGUGUAUAUGUGUGUUUGUCUGCUGUCCAAUAACACCAAAAGUGGAACUUAAGAAGCUUUGUGUUUUCAUAAGCACCCUGCCAGACACUUAACUCUUCUACUCAUGGAAGCCUUAGAUCUACAAUUUAGCUAUGCAAAUUAUUUUAAUAAUUUAAAAAUAGCAGUUCCAACCAGUGCUUUCUCUUUCAGAUGCAUCCCAAGAAUGGAUGGUGAAGGGACUCAGUUGGAGUGAGCUCUCAGGUUGAGGCUGGUGCAGUAGGAGUGAGCUAGACUGAAUCUCCAAUUUAUGGGACACACUCAGAACCUGGGUUACACUGAUGCCUCUCAGGCCCUGGAGCACUGGGAUCCCAGAGAUGCAUGUGUGCAUGUGUAUGUCUGUGUGUGUGUGUUGUCGGGAGAAGGGGGUAGUAUUUCUGUGUUCACUUCUAGGAAAUCACUGUACUAGCCUCCAAGAAUCCGGAAACCUUCCCAGCCGGGAACUGAAACCAUUCCCUGGAGGGAUGGGCUUGGCUUUUGAAGUUGACAGAAAGUAAAUGGGUAUUCUGAGAGGCAGCACAUGCCUACUGUCUAUCCAGUGUUCCAGGGACUGGGUCUUGCUUCUACUCAGCAGAGGCCAUCAUUCUGGGAGGCUGACCUGACUAGAGAAGGCUUUCUUUUAUAUGUGCAGUUUCUAUUGUGUAGAGGGGUUGGGGGUGGGAUCAUGGGAAAUUGGAGUGCUACCAGGUCCAUGGUUUUUGCUUUUUUUUUUUUUUUUUUUUUUUUUUUUUUUUUUUAAAGAAAAUAACCUGAAAACACUUCUGACUUUUCCACUGUCUCUUUAUAUGUGCUGAUAGGCAAAUGUGCAUGCACACCAAACAUAAGCAUGUUUGUGAGGGAAGCAGGAAGUAUCUCAGAGCCUAAGAACCAUGUUUUAUAGUUUCUUUGAUCAUAAACACUUGGUGGUGUCUUCCACCCAUUAUCCAGGCCUGAGGGGGGCAGGGUGGCUGGUGAUAAGAGGGAGGGCAGAAAAUCAGGCCUAGGCGUUUUCCCUUACCAUUGUCUUCCAUGGAAUGUUUUCAAGGGCCUCUCAAGCCCCAUUCAUCUGGUUUAGCCAAGUUCUCAGCCUGGGGAACACAGUACUACUUAAUGAUUGAGGUUUACCAUUUAUAGUGAUGCUUGAUUUCCUUUUCUUAAUAUAUUUGUAGAUAAAAAUUGAACAGGGACAAAGUAGCUAUUUAAGAAAGGAAGUGAACCAUGUUGGGUCAUAUCAUUUUCUUUAGAUUGGAUAUCUAUGAAGUCCACACCCCUUUGAGUUAUGCUUUUUAGGCAUCUAUCUCAUCAUCUCCUGAUUUAAGGAUAAUUCUGUCUGGUCCUUGGAGCUCUCUUCCCUAGGAAUUAGUGUGUGGAGUCUCUAUAUGCUUGUGAUCCUUGGAGCUCUCUUCCCUAGGAAUUAGUGUGUGGAGUCUCUAUAUGCUUGUGAUUCACAACUAAAUAUGAAAUUUCUCAAUUCAGGAGCAGGAAGCAAAGUGCUGGGGUACAGUUUUGCAGAUUGGUUGAAACACUUAGCCAAACUUAAGUGGCCUGGGUAGGACCAUCACUCCCAAAGUUGUCAGCAGAGAAGGGCCCUCUGUGUGAGUCUAUUCAAACCUGGCAUUGCUCUGAAAUUGAGUCCUCAUCCCAUGGGGAAGGUCUUCUGGGGGCUUUACAUUCCUUGUUACUAGUGUUCUGGAUAUUACCUUCUGCUUCCCACUUCCUUUUUUUUUUUUUUGAGACAGAGUCUUGCUCUGUCACCCAGGCUUGAGUGCAAUGGUGUGAUCUUGGCUCCGUGCAACCUCCACUCCCGGUUUCAAGCGAUCCUCCUGCCUCAGCCUCCCAAGUAGCUGGGAUUACAGGUGCACACCACCAUGCCCAGCUAAUUUGUAUAUUUUUUAGUAGAGACGGGGUUUCACCACGUUGGCCAGGCUGGCCUUGAACUCCUGACCUCAAGUGAUCCACCCUCCUCGGCCUCCCAGUGAUGGGAUUACAGGCGUGAGCCACUGCUCCUGGCCCCCACUUCCUUUUGAUUUCUCAGAUCAGUCUUUCCCUUCUGAGCCAUGGCCUUCUGUGCACCCAGCUCAGUGGCUCUUCACCCCUAAAACUAAGUGAAGUCAUCCUUCCCCAAAAGGACCCCUGGGAGAUGUUCUGGCCCUCUGCUGACUACUCCCAGGAAUCAGCACCUCAAGGACUAUUUGAGAAUGUUGUGCUCUCUAUUGGUCACCUUGAGACUCCGUUCCCCUGCUGCCAACUCUUCUCUUCUGCCCUGUGUAUUCUGCUGUGAUCCCCUUAACGGCUUUUCUGUGCUACUAGCUUAGCCCUAGGCCUUUUAUGAAUACCUGAGUCUUAUAACAAUGAACUUCUUGAGCAGGCAGUGUCCAACUUCUUUGCUCUUCAGGGACCUGAGUGUGCACCUUUCCCUUUUGCAGGUCUAUUUGACAUAGUAAUCUAGUGUGUUGGGGAGGGGUAGCCAAGCAGGCUGCAGUGUCUGCAAUGCAGAGGGCUUGGGGAGGUUUGGGUACUCUCUGCUGCCACUACUGGGAUGAUAUUCAGAAGAGAGAGGACCUCAUACUGUGACUGGACCCAGGACCCUCCCUGGAAGAGAGCUCAGCCCAGCUGUGUGUGUGUGUGUGUGUGAGUGUGUGUGUGUGUGUUUGUGUGCUGUGCUCAUGUGCACCUGGGUGUAAAAUGACUGUUAUCUGGUUGUGUUACUCAGGGUGGGCUGGGGACUCACCAGAAGAAUCCCCCCCAGCCUGCCCAAGACAGGUUUUUCCCUUGUACCAUCUUCAGAGAGGUCAGGGGAAGAGGGUCCAGGUGGGUUAAGGGGGGUCGCUAUGGAUAACCACUAAGACCAGACUGCUGCCAGGAGGAGUGGGGGAUAAUGAGGUGGCCCCAGGGUCCUGGCACCUGGCUUUGGUUUUCCGUCUUCUUUCCUCAGGACGCCCCUGAGGCCUGGGACCUGUGCCUGGCUUCGAGGAGCAUCUGUGGCUGGGUGAUCCAGCUGCUGGUGUGAUCAUGGGCUUCCCUCCUCUCAGCAGGGCAGGCGCUCCUGCCCCAGAGACUGGGCAACUGGCUGUUUCUAUGACGUAUUUAUUUUUACUUGUGUUUCAUGUCACUUUUUUAAAAAAAAGCAAACAGAACAAUUGUAAGUCAGUAUAACUGCCUAUCAGUUUUCUUUAUUUCUCUUUUUGUAAAAUAAAAUUUAAACUCAA